GUUGCCAAGGAGCUCGACUCUGGGAGCGGUCUAGAGCCCGGGCGCCUCCUGGGGGGUGGGGAAACGGUUUCGUGAGGAGAAUUUGAGGUAACCUCGCCAACUCGCGGUCGGAAGCUCCUCUGAACCCCGAAAUAGGAGAGAGCUCCCGUCCUCUCUCGGUCCUGAUGCAGCACCUCGCAAGUGGAAGGGGUCGUCGCGGUUAAGCCCCCGGAUAGGGGAAUCGGGCCCCUUCUGGGAUUCGAGCGGAUCCAGGCCGCUCCCUGGAGGGAUGAACUGUCGAGGGGCCCAGGGCAGCCCCCGCUAGAGGCCCGGUCGGGUGUGGGGUCCCCUGUCCCCUGUCCCGAGCCCGGGGAGGGGGACACUAUUUCUGGUACUCCCAGGAGGCUGCGGGUCGAUGCUCGUGCCAGCCUGGGACCCAGGCAGCACGGUUUCUCUCCCAAAUUGUGCCAGAGAACACGCACGUCCUGGUUUUCAUUGUUCCCCGCCUCCUGCGACUCGUUUGUGGGUGAGUGCUUGGGAAUUAGCGCGGCGACUUCGCGCUAGAAGAGGGACAGUAAUUGCUUUUGCUAAUUUUAGAGCGCAGAGCCCGCUGGGCACAGACAGCCUUCCUGUUCAGUACAUCUUUGUCCUUAUCGAGUGACCAUUUUUGCAGGCUGGUGGGCGACUUGGGGGGAACCCAACUGGUUUAUUUUGCCUUCCUGGAAACGUUGUACUAGUUUAUCCAGAUUUUUUUUUAAGGGAAAAAAGAGUAGACCUAUAGAUAAUUUCUAAAUCAUUUAAAAUGAAAUACAUAUUUCUGCACGCAAAGGUUAUGACGUGGACUUUUACUUAAAAUACUUUAAACAAUGGAAAACUUGCACUUCCAAUAUGGAUUUUAAAAAAAAACUUACGUAAAGGUUUUCCUUUUAUAGCUUAAAGGAAACCUCAGAUUUAUUAUAAGCCAUGGUGGUUAUCCUUCCUAUCCUCUUUUGACUUAUUUCUUAGCAAUAAUAAUUAUUUGUGCGUAAUUUUUCAUCAUUGUGGAGAAAUUAUCUUUUUUAUUUUAUUUUUUCUGUUGAGACGGAGUCUCUCUCUGUCCCCCAGGCUGGAGUGCAGUGGCGCGAUCUCGGCUCACUGCAACCUCCGCCUCCCGGGUUCAAGCAAUUCUCCUGCCUCAGCCUCCCAAGUAGCUGGGACUACCGGCGCCCGCCACCACACCUGGCUAAUUUUUGUAUUUUUAGUAGAGACCGGGUUUCACCAUGUUGGCCAGGCUGGCCUCGAACUCCUGACCUCAAGUGAUCUGCCUGCCUCGGCCUCCCAAAGUACUGGGAUUACAGGAGAGAACGACAGCUCCCGGCAGCAACUCAUUGCUUAAUUCAUUUUUAAUCCUUAAAGCAUUUACCUAGGUAAAGCUGUUUCAGCAGUUAAUAAAUCAGAUAUUCAGUUUUUUAAAAAGUUAUGAUCUUUCUCACUGCCAGCCUGAUUUCCUUUAGAUUUAGGCUUAUGUUGUACUUGUGCCUGUGAACAAGUUCAUUCAAUCUAGUGGAAGGAAUCACUGUUUUAGACACAAUGGAUGUUCAAAAAUGGAAUUGGACACAGAUACGGAAUUUACAGUUUAGCAGGGAAGAGAAGAUGCGUACCUAAAGAACUAGCACAAGAUCGGCCAGGCGCGGUGGCUCACGCCUGUAAUUCCAGCACUUUGGGAGGCCAAGUUAAAAUUAUAAGACCUAAUUAUGAGUGAUCAAAUUAAAUUCAUUAUGGACAGUCUCAAUAAGGAGCCCUUUAGGAAGAACUAUAAUUUAAUCACGUUUGAUUCCUUGGAGCCAAUGCAACUAUUACAAGUUCUCAGUGAUGUUCUGGCUGAGAUUGACCCAAAGCAACUUGUGGAUAUCAGAGAGGAGAUGCCAGAGCAGACAGCCAAACGAAUGUUGAGCCUUCUUGGUAUUCUUAAGUACAAACCUUCAGGAAAUGCCACAGAUAUGAGUACUUUUCGUCAGGGUUUGGUGAUUGGAAGUAAACCUGUAAUUUACCCAGUGCUCCACUGGCUUCUUCAGAGGACUAAUGAACUGAAGAAAAGAGCAUAUUUAGCUCGUUUUUUAAUAAAACUUGAGGUACCAAGUGAGUUUCUUCAGGAUGAAACUGUGGCUGACACCAAUAAACAGUAUGAAGAGUUAAUGGAAGCCUUUAAAACUUUGCAUAAAGAAUAUGAGCAGCUCAAGAUAUCUGGAUUUUCUACAGCAGAAAUAAGAAAGGAUAUCAGUGCAAUGGAAGAAGAAAAGGAUCAGCUCAUUAAGAGAGUUGAACAUUUGAAGAAAAGGGUUGAGACAGCUCAGAAUCAUCAAUGGAUGCUUAAAAUAGCAAGGCAACUUCGAGUUGAAAAAGAGAGAGAAGAAUAUCUUGCACAACAGAAACAGGAACAAAAGAAUCAGCUAUUUCAUGCAGUGCAAAGAUUGCAAAGAGUACAAAACCAGCUGAAAAGCAUGCGCCAAGCUGCAGCAGAUGCAAAGCCUGAAAGUUUAAUGAAGAGGCUAGAGGAGGAGAUAAAAUUUAAUUUAUAUAUGGUAACUGAAAAAUUUCCUAAAGAAUUAGAAAAUAAGAAAAAGGAAUUACAUUUUUUACAAAAAGUAGUUUCAGAGCCAGCUAUGGGCCAUUCUGAUCUUCUUGAACUUGAAUCUAAAAUAAAUGAAAUAAACACAGAAAUUAACCAGUUGAUUGAAAAGAAAAUGAUGAGAAAUGAGCCCAUUGAAGGCAAACUCUCACUGUAUAGGCAACAGGCAUCUAUCAUUUCCCGUAAAAAAGAAGCCAAAGCUGAGGAACUUCAGGAGGCCAAGGAGAAGUUAGCCAGCCUAGAGAGAGAAGCAUCAGUAAAGAGAAAUCAGACCCGUGAAUUUGAUGGUACUGAAGUUUUAAAGGGAGAUGAGUUCAAACGAUAUGUCAAUAAACUUCGAAGCAAGAGUACAGUUUUCAAAAAGAAGCAUCAGAUAAUAGCUGAACUUAAAGCUGAAUUCGGUCUUUUGCAGAGGACUGAAGAACUUCUUAAGCAACGUCAUGAAAAUAUUCAACAACAACUGCAAACUAUGGAGGAGAAAAAGGGUAUAUCUGGAUAUAGUUACACCCAAGAAGAGCUAGAAAGAGUAUCUGCACUGAAGAGUGAAGUUGAUGAAAUGAAAGGACGAACAUUGGAUGAUAUGUCUGAAAUGGUGAAAAAACUGUAUUCAUUGGUAUCUGAAAAGAAGUCAGCUCUUGCCUCAGUUAUAAAAGAGCUACGACAGUUGCGUCAAAAAUAUCAAGAACUGACCCAGGAGUGUGAUGAAAAGAAAUCCCAGUAUGAUAGCUGUGCAGCAGGCCUCGAAAGCAAUCGGUCCAAAUUAGAACAGGAAGUUAGAAGACUCCGUGAAGAAUGUCUUCAAGAAGAAAGUAGAUACCAUUAUACAAAUUGUAUGAUUAAGAACCUAGAAGUUCAACUUCGUCGUGCUACUGAUGAGAUGAAGGCAUAUAUCUCUUCUGAUCAACAAGAAAAAAGAAAGGCAAUUAGGGAACAGUAUACCAAAAAUACUGCUGAACAAGAAAACCUUGGAAAGAAACUUCGGGAAAAACAAAAAGUUAUACGAGAAAGUCAUGGUCCAAAUAUGAAACAAGCAAAAAUGUGGCGUGAUUUGGAACAAUUAAUGGAAUGUAAGAAACAGUGCUUUCUGAAACAACAAAGCCAAACUUCCAUUGGUCAGGUAAUUCAGGAGGGUGGGGAGGACCGGCUAAUACUGUGAAUUCUUGUGUCAUCGUUUGGGGUUUUACUUGAUACCACUAGCUAUAAGCCUAAUCUCAUAAUGUAUUUCUUUUUUGAAACUGAUUUGUAUAGCAUUUUGUUUUCAGAAGAGCCAUUCUUUAUUAAGUUUUCAUAGAAAAUAAUGUUAAGGUAGAUUUAGUUUGAAUGUUUUUUCAUAUGAAAAAGAGGCUUUUAUUCUUUUCCAUAGUUUAGACAUCACUGGCGUCUUCUGAGUUUUAUGAGACAGGAAACUAAGUUUACUAUCUGUAAAUGUAAACAUAUGUCCAUUAAGAAACAUGUAGUUUUUUUUUAGAAUGUAAUAACCCAGUGGCUUACUGUUUUUCUUAAUCUCUUUUAAAAAAACUUUAGAAGAAUCUUUUAGGAACUAAUAUCUCUUGUUCUGAAGAAACAUUUAUCUGACGUUCAGCAGUUCCUACAGUUUUACUUCAGUUUAUUUUUCUUCUGUAAAAUGCAAGAAAAUUUAAUAUUUUGACUAACAUGUCUUUUCUGUUUGUAUCAUUUAAAGGCAAAUAAACUUGGUACGUAUUUCAUAUCUAUUUAAAAAAUG